GACCCGGAAGCGGAUCUCGCGGGGCUACUGGCGCUCUCGGCCCACACAAUAUGACCUCGGGGAGGAUGCGAGGAAGAUGAACUGUGAUGAUCCACUUCUUCUUAAUGAAUGACUGACUUACCUGAGAAAGAAACUCAGAGGAAGAGGAAAGAAAGAAGAGGAGGGAAUGGCUCUUUCUCAGGGACUGUUUACAUUCAAGGAUGUGGCCAUAGAAUUCUCUCAAGAGGAGUGGGAGUGCCUGGACCCUGCCCAGAGGGCCUUGUACAGGGACGUGAUGUUGGAGAACUACAGGAACCUGCUUUCUCUCGAUGAGGAUAACAUCCCUCCAGAAGAUGGUUCUCACCUUGCAGCCUGUGGACAGAGCACACUGCCUCUUCCUUAGAAUCCUACAAAAUCCGACCCUUUUAUUUUACUCCCGUACCUUUUAUUUCUCUCCCUUUUCUAGCUUUCUACUCUAUCCGGGAACUUAGGGAGACCUUAGUCUUCCUGAUUCCAUAUUCUUCUAAGAUUUGCCUCUGAAAGUUGCUUUUGAAAUACACAUUCCGGAUGGGCGUGGUGCCUCACGCCUAUAAUCCCAGCACUUUGGGAGGCCGAGGUGGGCAGAUCACCUGAGGUCGGGAGUUCGAGACCAGCCUGACUAACAUGGAAAAACCCCGUCUCUACUAAAAAUACAAAAAUUAGCCGGGUGUGUUGGCGCAUGCCUGUAAUACCAGCUGCUCGGGAGGCUGAGGCAGGAGAGUUGCUUGAACCCGAGAGGCAGAGGUUGUGGUGAGCCGAGAUCACGCCAUUGCACUCCAGCCUGGGCAACAAGAGCAAAACUCCAUCUCGAAAAAAAAAAAAAGAAAAAGAAAAGUACACAUUCCUAGAGUCUGAAAUUUCCUCUCUUUCUGCUGUGAUAACCCACCAAUAGGCGAUGGACAACUUUUGGUGGACUCUCCCAUGGAAGAGGUUUCCUUGGUGACAGAACAUUCUUGAAAGAGAACAUUAAUUAAUCUGUCACAGUAUCAUUCUGCUACAUAGAGGUGCCUCUUGAAGCCACUGAGUAGAGUAGCCUGCAUGUCCCAGUAUGCUGAGAGAGAAUCAGGACAGCCGGAGGGAUAAGUGCUUCUGACCUUCUGGUUUCUGUGGAGUUUCCAGUGUCUCCCAAGGGCAGUGUGACAACGCUGGUUAGAUAUAUGCUGAUCAUCCUCUUGGAGCCAGCAGUACAAGGUGUAGGAGUUUCUCCUGGGAAGAGCAUUCUCCAAGUUCUCAACCUCAUAUCUGCGAACAUGUUGACCAAACUGUUGCUCAUACCACAUUAUUCAUCCCAUACGUGCAGUUGUACAUUUUUCUUCAGUAUGAUUUUUAUGCCUUUAUUGAGGGAGCUUACAAAGUUGAAUUAGGCAUACAUUUUUAAAGUUCAGUAUAAUUUGGUUAAGCCACUGACACUUUCAUUUUGCCAAUGUCAUUGGUAUAAAUGAACUUGUAUGUAUUUAAUCAGCAGUUACAUGUUUUCAUGAUACUCUUAGUGUUUUUUGUUUUAUAUCUACAGUGUGUGGGGCCAUGAGAUGAAUGAAUAUUGUUUUAUUAUAUAUAUUUUUUUCUGCUUCAUAUACUUUCAUGAUGUUUUAUAUGUUUUACCAGAAGAUUUCUUCCUUGAGUAUUUAUGUCUGAGUAUUAGUUUCCUCAAAACAUAUAUAACCUCCAAAACUUUGUUAAAGGAUAGUAUUAGUUAUUCCUUUUACUUCUGUUUCCUGUAACUUUAUAUCAACUCUUAGCUUAUACUUUUUAAAAAUAGACUUUCUAUUUUUUAGCAAUUUUAUGUUCACAGCAAACUAGAUUUCCUGUAUACUCUGUUCCCCCACACGUGCACAGCGUCUUCCCCCAUUAUCACCAUCCCCCAUCACAGUGGUACAUUUGUUAAAAUUGAUAAACCUACAUUGACACAUCAUUAUCACCCAAAGUCCAUAGUCGAUGUUGGGGUUCACUCUAUGUAUAUGCUUUGGGUUUGGGCAAAUAUAUAAUAGACAUAUAUCCUCCAUAAUAGUAUCUUACAGAAUAAUUACACUGCCCUAAAAAAUCUGUGCUCUGUCUGUUCAUCUCUCCCUCCCCCCAGCACCUGGCAACCACUGAUCUCUUUACUGUCUCCAUAGAUUUGCCUUUUUCAGAAUGUCAUAUAGUUGGAACCAUAUAGUAUAUGGCCUUUUCAGAUUGGCUUCUUUCACUUAAUAAUAUGCAUUUCAAUUUCUAGGGCUGGGCGUGGUGGCUCACGCCUGUAAUCCCAGCACUUUGGGAGGCCGAGGCCGGCGGAUCACGAGGUCAGGAGAUCAAGACGAUCCUGGCUAACAUGGUGAAACCCCGUCUCUACUAAAAAUACAGAAAAUAAGCCGGGCGUGGUGGCGGGCACCUGUAGUUCCAGCUACUCAGGAGGCUGAGGCAGGAGAAUGGCGUGAACCUGGGAGGCAGAGGUUGUGAUGAGCCGAGACCAUGCCACUGCACUCCAGCCUGGGCAACAGAGCGAGACUCCAUCUCAAAAAAUAGAUAAAUAAAAUAAAUUUCUUCCAUGUCUUUUUAUAGCUUGACAGCUCAUUUCUUUUUAGCACAGAAUAACAUCCCUUCAUUGCACACACUGUGUAAAGAAUGACUCCUGCUUAUACACAGGACAGCUUACUCAGGACAGCAACAUGAUCUGGUCACUGUCUAAACAACUUGUGCAAGAUAAGGUGACUUAAAUGCUAUCUGAGAGCAGUGGUGCUGUCACACUAUAGGUGACACAGCUCAGGUCCCAUAAUCUGCCUUGAAACAUUUCUUCCUACACUCCUCGUAUUUGCUGUGAUUUAUAAUCCGUGCUGCCCUGGGUGGCCAGUGGUGCUUAAUGCUGUGAACAUGGCAUCUUAGCCCGCACACACAGGUUCAGAUUCUGGCUUUCAGAUGUGCUUUCUCUGUGAGUUAGGGAUAGAUAUGUAAACCUCUUCAGCCCUUUGUUUUGGUAUGAAAAGGUGCGAUAAUUUACCUCAAGAGGAUUUACAUCAAUUAGUGCUGUUAGAGACCUUAGUAACUUGCAUAGCAUUUAGUAUGCUUUGAAAAGUUACCUUUAUGAAUAAGAUAUGUCAAGUGUCUGUCAUGUUUCUUAUGAGAUUGACCUUUGCCUUCAUUAUAUCUUACAUAUUUUCUUUUUUGUAAUUUUUUUUUUCAUAUCAACAUUUCUCUGACUCUACAUAAUAAAAUGUUAAAGCACACAGCUUUCAUUAUAUGUAUUUUUUGGCCAUAGAACUGGAAAACUAGAUGACAUUUCCUAGUCAGGGAGUUUCUCUAUAUACUGCUGUCAUAUAACUGCAGGCAUGAAAUUAUUUCAGACUCCCCUCCUAAUUCUUCAUCUUUAUAGUAAUGUGCAUUUACCUGAAGCUGAUAUUUCAAAAUUUAGUGAUUCUCAACAUAUUAUUUUUCCUAUUGUGUGUCCCUUCUGUUUUUUCUGUAGUUCAUAAGCAGUAAUUCUUUAGAAUUUCACUGACAAUUUUGUGUAAUUGUGGUUGUUCAUUAACUUGCCUGUUAGAUUUUCACAGGUUACUAAAGUGUUUUAUUUAUUUUUGUAAUGAUUUACAGAUGAUGGUUUUUCAGUAUAUAUUAUGCAAUAGAACCACCAUGCACAAAUUGUUAAUGCUGCAAAAUGCACAUUCUACAUGGGUGUAAGUAGUUUUAUAACAAGUACUCACAUUUGCAAUUUGUAAAUAUUCAAAAUUUUAUUAAAUUCUUCCGAAUUUUUUCUUUCAGUGUUUUGUUUGCAAUUAUGAAUUGUCAUUUUUAAAUAUUUUUUAUUAGAUAAGCUUGAGCUGUGCCUUACCUUUUGUGUGUAAUAAUUAUGUACUAAAUAAUGCAUUACUAUUUGUUUAUCUUCAAAUAUGAGACUACCAUAUAGCUAUGCCAAUUUACGUGUUCCUUGGAGUGGUGGUGGAAAAAUACCUCUUCUUUCAGAGUUUAUGUGGAUUUACAUAGUAUGAGUGUUUUAGCUAUAGGGUGUUUUAAACUGUGCUUAAAAUAAUUUGUUACAUGUUUUGUUACUGUGUUACUUUAUUGAGGACAGCUAGUCCCUUUGUGUUGUUAAACGUUUAAAGACAGUUGAGAAGCUUCAUAACUCUGUUCAUUGUAAAUCUUAGCUUUCUUGUAAUAUGUAUUUUAAUAAAAUAUUUACCUUGCAACUCUA